AUUAUCUGCUGAUCCAGGCCAUGCACGACCUGCCCCCUGACUCGGGCGCGCGGCGGGGCGGCAGGGGCUUGGCGGAUCACAGCUUCCCCGCGGGAGCCCGGGCUCCGGGCCAGCCGCCUUCCCGCGGCGCCGCGUACCGCCGAGCCUGCCCCCGGGACGGGGAGCGGGGAGGCGGCGGACGCCCUCGGCAGCAGGUGUCCCCGCCCCGGUCGCCUCAGAGGGAGCCGCGGGGAGGCCAGCUGCGGACUCCUCGGAUGCGGCCGUCCUGCAGCAGAAGCCUCGAGAGCCUCCGGGUGGGUGCCAAGCCGCCUCCCUUCCAGCGGUGGCCGAGCGACAGCUGGAUCAGGUGCGGCGCGCACCGGGACUGGGACGAGCCCCCGCCACGUGGAGGCAGGAUGGACGGCUGGAGUGGGGACCGCGCCCGGGCGGCUGCACCCACCGGCCUCCAGCCUCCAGGCUGCAAGGACCACGGCUGCUCCUCGGGAAGCCCUUUCAGGGAUCCAGCGGGGUCCUCUGUGAUACGCAGUGGCAAAGGAGACCGCCAGGAAGGCCCCUCCUUCCUCAGGCCGCCGGCAGUGACAGUCAAGAAGCUGCAGAAGUGGAUGUACAAAGGGCGUCUGCUGUCCCUGGGAAUGAAGGGUCGUGCCCGUGGGACGGCUCCCAAAGUCACAGGAACGCAGGCAGCCUCCCCAAAUGUGGGCGCUUUGAAAGUGCGUGAAAACCGUGUCCUGUCGGUGCCUCCAGACCAAAGAAUUACGCUGACAGAUUUAUUUGAAAAUGCCUAUGGGUCUUCAAUGAAGGGAAGAGAACUUGAAGAGCUGAAGGAUAAUAUUGAAUUCAGAGGUCAUAAGCCACUUAACAGCAUCACUGUUUCAAAGAAACGCAAUUGGCUAUAUCAGAGUACUCUGAGGCCUCUUAAUCUGGAAGAAGAAAAUAAGAAAUGCCAAGAUAGAAGUCAUUUAUCCAUCUCACCUGUGUCUCUACCUAAACAUCAGCUAUCACAGUCUUUCCUCAAAUCAUCUAAAGAGUACUGUACAUAUGUGGUAUGUAACGCUACAAACUCUUCAUUAUCGAAAAACUGUGCUUUAGAUUUUAAUGAGGAAAAUGAUGCAGAUGAUGAAGGAGAAAUAUGGUACAAUCCCAUUCCUGAGGAUGAUGACCUUGGUAUAUCAAGUGCCUUGAGUUUUGGUGAGGCCGACUCUGCUGUUCUGAAGCUCCCUGCUGUCAAUUUGAGCAUGUUGUCUGGCAGUGACCUGAUGAAAGCAGAGCGGCAUACUGAAGACUCACUGUGCUCUUCCGAACAUGCAGGUGAUAUUCAGACCACACGGUCAAAUGGAAUGAAUCCUAUACAUCCUGCCCAUUCCACAGAAUUUGUGCAGCAGUACAAGCAAAAGCUAGGACACAAGACACAAGAAGGUAUAAUGGUGGAGGACAGUCCCAUGUUGAAAUCUCCUUUUGCAGGUUCUGGGAUCCUGGCUGCUACAAAUAGUACUGAAUUGGGAAUUAUGGAACCAUCUUCUCCAAAUCCUAGCCCUGUGAAAAAAGGCAGUUCAAUUAAUUGGUCAUUGCCAGAUAAAAUAAAAUCUCCACGAACUGUGAGGAAACUUUCCAUGAAAAUGAAAAAGUUGCCAGAAUUUAGCCGAAAGCUAAGCGUUAAGGGAACAUUGAAUUAUAUAAACAGUCCAGAUAAUACUCCUUCUUUGUCUAAAUAUAACUGCCGAGAAGUUCAUCAUACUGAUAUUCUGCCCUCUGGGAACACAACCACCGCUGCUAAGAGGAAUGUUAUAAGCCGAUACCAUCUUGAUACCAGUGUAUCCUCCCAGCAGAGCUACCAGAAGAAAAACUCUAUGAGUUCUAAGUAUUCCUGCAAAGGUGGUUACCUUAGUGAUGGAGACUCACCUGAACUUACAACUAAAGCUAGCAAACAUGGAUCUGAAAACAAAUUUGGAAAAGGAAAAGAAAUAAUUUCAAAUAGUUGUAGCAAGAAUGAAAUAGACAUUGAUGCUUUUAGGCAUUAUAGCUUUUCUGAUCAACCUAAGUGUUCACAGUACAUAUCUGGGCUCAUGAGUGUACAUUUCUAUGGUGCUGAGGAUUUAAAACCACCUCGGAUAGAUUCAAAAGACGUCUUUUGUGCAAUUCAGGUAGAUUCAGUAAACAAAGCAAGAACAGCUUUGCUCACAUGCCGAACAACAUUUUUAGACAUGGAUCACACUUUCAACAUAGAAAUUGAAAAUGCACAACAUUUGAAACUAGUAGUAUUCAGUUGGGAACCCACUCCAAGAAAAAAUCGAGUUUGUUGUCAUGGAACUGUUGUUCUUCCCACCUUAUUUAGAGUGACAAAGACUCAUCAGUUGGCUGUCAAACUUGAACCUAGAGGUCUUAUUUAUGUGAAAGUGACUCUUAUGGAACAGUGGGAGAAUUCUCUUCAUGGACUAGAUAUAAACCAAGAACCAAUAAUAUUUGGAGUUGAUAUUCAAAAAGUUGUAGAGAAAGAAAAUAUAGGACUGAUGGUGCCCCUUCUGAUACAGAAAUGUAUUAUGGAAAUUGAAAAGAGAGGCUGUCAGGUAGUAGGCCUGUAUCGAUUAUGUGGUUCGGCAGCAGUCAAGAAAGAACUGCGAGAGGCUUUUGAGAGAGAUAGCAAAGCUGUUGGUCUGUGUGAAAACCAGUACCCAGAUAUAAAUGUAAUAACAGGUGUUCUUAAGGAUUAUUUAAGAGAACUCCCUUCUCCUCUGAUAACAAAGCAGCUUUAUGAGGCUGUAUUAGAUGCAAUGGCAAAAAGUCCUUUGAAAAUGUCAUCAAAUGGUUGUGAGAAUGACCCAGGUGACUCUAAGUACACUGUUGACCUGCUGGAUUGUCUGCCAGAGAUUGAGAAGGCAACCCUAAAGAUGUUGUUGGAUCAUUUGAAAUUGGUGGCUUCCUAUCAUGAAGUGAAUAAGAUGACGUGCCAGAAUUUGGCUGUGUGCUUUGGACCAGUAUUAUUAAGUCAGAGGCAAGAGCCUUCCACCCAUAACAACAGAGUCUUUACUGAUUCAGAAGAACUUGCAAGUGCUUUGGAUUUUAAAAAACACAUUGAAGUUCUUCAUUACUUACUCCAACUCUGGCCAGCGUUUAACUGUCAAAAAAUCAACAGACAAUUUAUUCCCAGAGCAGAAGUCUUCUCUGAAUUAUCUGAGGCAGAAGAAAGAACGACCUCAUAUGUUAAAUUUGAGUGGUACUGAUUCAUCAGGAGUACUUAGGCCAAGGCAAAACCGAUUAGACAGUCCACUUAGCAAUCGUUAUGCAGGAGACUGGAGCAGCUGUGGGGAAAACUACUUUUUAAAUACAAAAGAAAAUUUAAAUGAUGUGGAUUAUGAUGAUGUCCCUUCAGAAGAUAGAAAAAUCGGAGAAAAUUAUAGCAAAAUGGAUGGGCCAGAAGUAAUGAUUGAACAGCCAAUUCCCAUGUCCAAAGAGUGUACAUUUCAGACAUAUUUGACAAUGCAGACAGUUGAGUCUACAGUGGAUCGAAAAAACAAUCUCAAAGAUCUACAAGAAAGUAUUGAUACUUUGAUUGGAAAUCUGGAACGUGAGCUCAACAAAAACAAGCUUAAUAUGAGUUUUUGAGAUUGAGGGUUUUUUUUUGUAAUGUCUUAAAGUUUCAAAUCUGUUUUUGUUUUAUUUUCUUAUACCACCCACAGCGAUGUUUUCAUUUUUUUACUCUUGAAAUCUUUAAUUAAUUUUUAAUAAGUUUAUCUGAUUCAAUUAAAAACACUAUUCAUUAAUACAAUUUUUACUUAUCUCACUAGAAAACUUUUCUGGGGAUCAAUAAAACUUGGACUUCUUGGGAUAUUUUACUAAAUCUUGCCAACUCUAUGGAGAUAACUUUCAAAUGCACUUAAGAAGGUUCACAUAAGUUAUUAGCCCCUCAAGGUUUUUCUGCUUUAUGGGAACCACUCUUCUGUAGCUGAGACAGAUGUCCUUUUUUUUGUUGUUUUUUGAGACAGAGUCUCACUCUGUCGCCCAGGCUGGAGUGCACUGGUGCGAUCUCAGGUCACUGCAACCUCCACCUCCCUGGUUCAAGUGAUUCUCCUGCCACAGCCUCCCGAGUAGCUGUGAUGACGGGGCCCACCACCAUGCCCAGCUAAUUAUUGUAUUUUUAGUAAAGAUGGGGUUUCACCAUGUUGGCCAGGCUGGUCUCGAACUCCUGAUCUCAGAUGAUCCGCCCACCUUGGCCUCCCAAAGUGCUGGGAUUACAGGCGUGAGCCACUGCGCCUGGCCUCUAGAUGUUCUUUUAGAGGAACAUCACAGCUGCUCAGUCUGAUUUGCAGUACUGGUCCUGGUACACUGCAACAUCCUUUGGUCAAAUUUUAUUUGUAAUGCAAAUGCUGCUAUAAGAAAAUCUUUUUAUAAAUAAAAGUGAAAUUAUACAAGUAUUAAUGUUUUCUGUAUUAACAGUAAUUAUUUAAGCUUAUAAAAAUUAAAUAUUUUUAUAAUCCUGAAACUGUAUAUAUUUAUAAAUGCAUAUAUGUAUAGAUAUCAGGAUGGGGGAGGGGUUAUUGUAGAAUCACAUGUAUUUUUAAAGUAUAUAUGUCAUGAGGCCAAAAUUAUUAUCUUAAAGUAUUUUUUUCAGGGAAAGAACAUUUAAAUUAAAGGAGGAAUUACAUAAAAACACUUGAACAAUAAUACUCUAGAAGCAUCUGAAUAGAAAUAAUAGACUUUCUUUCCUUUAUUCACAGAAAGUCACAAUGUCCCCUGGGAAAAGUCAUCUUUUAAAUUUGAAAUCCUCUAACUCCUUAAGGGAUUAAGUACCCAGAUUUCUGCACUGGUGACUUAGAUUUAAUAAAUCUGCUCCUGUUCUAUGCAUUUUUAUAUUCUGCUUUGUUUUAAUUAUUUAUUUGUAGUAGUACAUUUAUAACAUUGACUUUAUAAUUACCCCCAUUUGUUUCUAAAUAGUCUUGCCAGCAUAUUACAUGUUACUGAUUUUUAAAAAUUAACUUAUUUUGGCUAAGUAUAUAUACAAUGUUAUAGAAUCACAGUAAUGUUUGAAAAUGUAAAUUUAGAAGGCUUUUGUAUUAAAUCAAAAUGUAUUUUUUUAACUUUUAUAUCUACAGAAUAUGUAAUUUUAAAAUUAUAAAUAGACUUUAAGUUACCAACUUUUAAGACAUGGCAGCCAUUGAAAAACUGGCUUCCUGAUGUUUUUCUAAAUAUUAAAGUACUUAAAAUAUUUCUAUGCAAUAAAUAUUGAUAAACAGACAUUAUUUAAUUUGAAAACCCAUUGUUAAAAAAGAUAAAUAUUUUUAUAUGAAAUUUUCAUUUUUUAAAACUUUGUGUUAACAAUUCAGAAGAAUACCAAGAGAACAUAUAUAUUGAGUAAACAGUCAAAGGAAAGUACUCUUGAAUGUUUUAUAGGAAAGCUGUCUCAGUUUCCUUCCUUUUGUUGCUAUAUCAUGUAUGAAUUGAAUAAAUUGCUCUAGAAAUGUAAAAAUUUUAUUAAAAUAUUAUAAUCUUCGUGUUAUGCUAUUAUAAUGGUUUUAAGGAUCACUUAUUUUAAUAUUCUUUUUAAGCAAAGGUGUUAAAAUUUUGGACCAUCAUGUAUUAUCCAUCAAUAUAUGUAAAUAACAUUUAUUUGUCCAGAAUUUUCCAGAAUCUGAAAUACUUUUAAGGGCCAUGCUUGUAUUACUAUAUUACUAUAUUAUUUUGGAUGAGAAUAGUUUUAAAGUUGAUCUCUGCCCUCUUAGAGAAUUCUAUCAUUUUUUUGUUGUCUCAUCACCGAGUUAUAGCUAUAAACUGCUUUUAUUGACUCUGCUGUACCAGAAGUGUUGGAUAAGUUUAGAUGUCUUUACUUUAAAUGGCAUUUUACUUCAAAUAUUUUUUGCGAGUUUUUAUACCUGCUUUUUAUAAUUUCCUAGGAUCUUUCUGUAGUGUCAACUGUUGCUCCUUUCUGAGGCUGCCAGCUUUAAUUUUUCUUUUUCUUUUCUUUUUUUUUUUUAAUAGAGACAAGAUCUCAGUAUAUUGCCCAGGCUGGUCUCAAAUUCCUGGGCUCAAGCGAUCCACCCGCCUCAGCCUCCCAAAGUGCAAGGAUUACAGGCGUGAGCCACUAUGCCCAGCCCCUAAUGUUUUUUAGGAUUAAAAACAAUUUUAAUUUUAGAGCAUGUACCUGAAUAAAAAUUCUAAACAAUUCAGAUGGAUAGAAAAUAAAAGUACAAGUGUUUCUGUCUGCCAUCCACACCAAUUUCACCUCUUAGAGGUUAACAGCACGUUUCUUGCUGCUGUUUCUUAUCAUUUAAGCCAAAUUUGUUAUUCUAUGAAUGAUAAACAGUUUAUCUCACUUCAUUCCUUCUCACCAUUUUUGUUAUGUUUUUAGUUCAUUUGUUCUCCUUUAUAACUGUAGUUAAUAAUUUUUUUGAUCCAUUGACUUUAAAUAUAUUUCCAUAACAUUGAGGAAAUGACCAACCUUGUACUUCCCUUCCAUUACUGUCCUUUACCUCCUAACUUCUCUUAAGUUAUACUAUUAGUUUAUAUAAUCAGUUUUAAUAGAUGUAUAGUUUUCCCUUUAUACUGUAUAUUUAUUUGUAUAUUGUAUAUACUGUAUACUGUAUAUUUAUUCUAAACACUGCAAAUCAGUAACUAGCAGUCACACUAUGCAAAAGUAUGCACAGGUAAACCAGGUGAUUUAUCUCCUUCUAUGUAUCUAUCUUAUAUCCUUAAGUCUGUGCUGAUUUAAGCAGAAUGCUUCAUACAUAAAGGCCAAAUGGAUUCUUUUAUAGCCAGUCGUCAACUUCCCCAAAUCAUGCCAUGUGUCAUUUGCUACGUAAUUGGGUCAUGGCUUUUGCAUACUUUAAUGGUUCCUGGAGUAAGUAAUUGCUUUUAUUUCUUUUUUUUUAAAAAAAAUCUUUCAAUAGAGACGGGGUAUUGUUAUGUUGCCAGGACUGGUCUCAAAUUUGUAGGCUCAAGCGAUCCUUUCCGCCUCAGUCUCCCAAAGUGCUGGGAUUACAGUAUGAGCCACUGCUUCCAGCCUGCUUUUAUUUCUCGACAGAAGAAAAACACUUGCUUUACUGUAGCUCUUCUUUUAAUCAUACUAUUGAAUUACCAGAUUUGUUCAGAGUGCUUUUAGCUCUCAUCUUGGGAUUCUGGAACUAUAUUCUUGUCUUUAUUUUUCUUUGACAGAAUUGACAGGAAGGAAGGAAGUAUGUUCUUCACUCUAACCCCGAGAUCAUUUUAUGCUUCUUAAUCAGCUUCAUCAAAUUAGGACAAAGUGAUUUUUAGCUAUCAUCUUGGGAUGUAUUUUCUUUGUACUCCUAUUUUUUUUUUCUUUCUUUUCUUUCUUUUCUUUUUUCUUUUUCUUUUCUUUUUUUUUUUUUUUUGCUGCAUUCUUUCUUGAAUUUGUCUUUUCUGUUUGCUGAAGUAUAUUUACAGGUGCCUUUUUUUCCCCCAGAAAGGGUGCAUGGGAGAGAAACUAGGAGUCCUUGUGUGUUUGACAAGGCCUUUAUUUUUUCCUCACACUUUAUUUUUAUUGGGCCUGCAGUUCUAUGUUCAAACUCAUUUUUCUUUAGAAUUUUGAAGACAUUUCACUAUUACCUUCAAGCAUCCAGUUUUGCAGUAGUCCAGGCUAGAAAGAUUCGGACAAGGAUAGAAACAAUAGAGAUGGUGAGAUAUGGUUGGAUUCUGGAUAUAUUUUGAAGCAGGAGCUAAAAGAAUCUGCCAGUGGACUAUGAAAGGAGUAGGGCCUGAGCAGCUGAAUGAUGGAGCGCCAUCAAAUGAGAUUGAAAUGACUCCAUGUUUUUUCAGUGAGUUCCUUCUAUUGGACGUUGGUGUUGUUAAUAUAGUAGUUAUUAAAAUGUCUUAUAAUGUCCUGUUAACGAUUAGUACUAAUGCCUCUGUACUUGGUGAUGGUGCUCAUAGAGUUACUACUAGAAUAAGAAGGCCAGAAGAGGUUGCAGUGAGCCGAGAUUGCGCCACUGCACUCCAGCCUGGGCGACAGAGCGAGACUCCGUCUCAAAAAAUAAAAAAUGAAAAAUAAAUAACUGUCUGGAAAAUUUUAGAUUAUGUAGCUUUACAUGUUAGGGACCCUAAAGAAACAAGGUUGAGUACUGGUAGGGUCCCUGAAAAGAAUUUAGUUUCCAGACCACAGAUUGAGUUUGAUGGUUAAGAUUUUAUAAAUUAAAUAUAUCAAUUUUUAGGUACUUUGGUAUGAUAAAGUUGUAUUAUGAUUAAUAAUAACAAGUCUUAAUUUGAGGCUUACUCACUUGAGGACUUUGGUACAAAAAUGCUCUUUUGCUGUUUUUCCUGACCAAUUUUCACUCUGAAUGCAAAAGGGUCAUAUGUGAUAAACACUGAAGUGCCACAAGUCAGAUUUCUUGAUUGCAUUCUGCCUCAGCCUGAAAUGGACUUGCUAACUCAGGCAGAAAUUGAAUUUGUUGAGAAAAUAGUGUAUCAAAGGGAAGACUUUGAGGGUGCUGAAAGUCUUUUAUAUUUUGGUCUAGGUGGUGGUUUCAUAGGUGUUUACAUAUCAGGUUGCAUACUUAAGAUUUGUGCCCUUUAUAUGUCAUACCUCUUUUUAAAUUUUUUUUAAUGGGCAAGCUUGAGAAAUAGACUUGGAAAAGAAACAGAAACUAAGAGAGGCUAGGUCGUCAGAAUGACAGCAAUCAAGGCCAUACCUGGUUAUGACACUGCUGUUGCUGUCACUGUCACUAAGCAGCCUCAUGUACUCCCCACUGGAGUUAGUUAGAAAACAUCCUCAUUCUCCAUUACUCCUGAUUCACAGUCCCAGACAGAAGCAUGAGAUUGUACUCCAGCUUCCAGGAGGCAGAGAGGAAUUAGCUUGCAUCCUUUCUUAGAAUUUACAUAGUAAGUAGAUUCUAUGAUCGCAGAAGGAGAUUUGGAUGCCGAGCAGGCAAAACAGUGACAAAUAUACACAACACUUUCCUAAUCAUCUGAACCCUGUUGCUCCAAAAUUGGAGUCUUUCUUACCCUGUCCCCCCUGUAUAUCCCAGCCAUCAACAGGUCUAAGUGCUGUGUGUCUUAAACUGCAUUGGAGUUUGUCACUGCUAAUACCCUAGUCCAAGCCACCAUCAUCCCUCAAUCUCAUAUUUCCUCUCUGCUAUCACUCUCCCCUCUCUACACCCACGAUCCAGUCUAUUCAUGGAAGCUACUAUGAAAAAGAUAUACUGCAUCAUUUCCUAGGCCUUCUCCCUUGCUCCCUGGCUCUAGCAACACUGGGGACCCUCAUUGCUGUCUGAGGCUCUCUGCUCUUGCCAUUGCCCCUGUCUGGAAAGCUCUUUAUCCAGAUGUUACUUAAGCAGUUCCUUUUUGUCAUUCGCUUCUCUGCUCAAAUGUCACUUCAAAGAGCCUGCUUCUGAACAGCCUGCUCUGAGAAUAAGGGGAAGAAGCAGAUGGAGAUUUCUGGGUUUUUUUGUAAUAAAUGCUAUUAAUAAAUACUUAUGGUACUAUCUGACUAAACUGCAGAUAUUUAUCACUUUGGUAAAUGUUUACAUUUAAACCAAAUUUAAGAAGAAAAAUGUUUAAAAAACUACACCCACAUCCAUUGUCACUUUUUGUCUAUCACCUGGGCUUCAAGGCUUUAUCAUUAUCUGAAAUUAUCUCAUUUAUUUAUUUGUUUAUUCAUUUAUUGUCUAUGUCCACUCCUGUAGAAUGUAAUCUCCAUGGCAGCAGGGACUUUGUAUAACAAUCUAGUUCAUUGCCAUAUGCCUAGGGACUAUAACAUAGAAGCUGUUCAAUUAAUUGUUAAUCAAUGAAUAACUGUAAUAAGAUACUUGAGAAUGGUUGUCUUUUUGUUAGGAAAAGACUAAGUACUAUAAUCGCAAUGUCUACAUAAUUUUAAAAAUAUUCACUCCUGAGUAAUAAAUUAUUUGUGGUUAAGAGA